CCUGCGUGCGCUGCCGUCCCGGAUCCACCGUGCCUCUGCGGCCUGCGUGCCCGGAGUCCCCGCCUGUGUCGUCUCUGUCGCCGUCCCCGUCUCCUGCCAGGCGCGGAGCCCUGCGAGCCGCGGGUGGGCCCCAGGCGCGCAGACAUGGGCUGCUCCGCCAAAGCGCGCUGGGCUGCCGGGGCGCUGGGCGUCGCGGGGCUACUGUGCGCUGUGCUGGGCGCUGUCAUGAUCGUGAUGGUGCCGUCGCUCAUCAAGCAGCAGGUCCUUAAGAACGUGCGCAUCGACCCCAGUAGCCUGUCCUUCAACAUGUGGAAGGAGAUCCCUAUCCCCUUCUAUCUCUCCGUCUACUUCUUUGACGUCAUGAACCCCAGCGAGAUCCUGAAGGGCGAGAAGCCGCAGGUGCGGGAGCGCGGGCCCUACGUGUACAGGGAGUUCAGGCACAAAAGCAACAUCACCUUCAACAACAACGACACCGUGUCCUUCCUCGAGUACCGCACCUUCCAGUUCCAGCCCUCCAAGUCCCACGGCUCGGAGAGCGACUACAUCGUCAUGCCCAACAUCCUGGUCUUGGGUGCGGCGGUGAUGAUGGAGAAUAAGCCCAUGACCCUGAAGCUCAUCAUGACCUUGGCAUUCACCACCCUCGGCGAACGUGCCUUCAUGAACCGCACUGUGGGUGAGAUCAUGUGGGGCUACAAGGACCCCCUUGUGAAUCUCAUCAACAAGUACUUUCCAGGCAUGUUCCCCUUCAAGGACAAGUUCGGAUUAUUUGCUGAGCUCAACAACUCCGACUCUGGGCUCUUCACGGUGUUCACGGGGGUCCAGAACAUCAGCAGGAUCCACCUCGUGGACAAGUGGAACGGGCUGAGCAAGGUUGACUUCUGGCAUUCCGAUCAGUGCAACAUGAUCAAUGGAACUUCUGGGCAAAUGUGGCCGCCCUUCAUGACUCCUGAGUCCUCGCUGGAGUUCUACAGCCCGGAGGCCUGCCGAUCCAUGAAGCUAAUGUACAAGGAGUCAGGGGUGUUUGAAGGCAUCCCCACCUAUCGCUUCGUGGCUCCCAAAACCCUGUUUGCCAACGGGUCCAUCUACCCACCCAACGAAGGCUUCUGCCCGUGCCUGGAGUCUGGAAUUCAGAACGUCAGCACCUGCAGGUUCAGUGCCCCCUUGUUUCUCUCCCAUCCUCACUUCCUCAACGCUGACCCGGUUCUGGCAGAAGCGGUGACUGGCCUGCACCCUAACCAGGAGGCACACUCCUUGUUCCUGGACAUCCACCCGGUCACGGGAAUCCCCAUGAACUGCUCUGUGAAACUGCAGCUGAGCCUCUACAUGAAAUCUGUCGCAGGCAUUGGACAAACUGGGAAGAUUGAGCCUGUGGUCCUGCCGCUGCUCUGGUUUGCAGAGAGCGGGGCCAUGGAGGGGGAGACUCUUCACACAUUCUACACUCAGCUGGUGUUGAUGCCCAAGGUGAUGCACUAUGCCCAGUACGUCCUCCUGGCGCUGGGCUGCGUCCUGCUGCUGGUCCCUGUCAUCUGCCAAAUCCGGAGCCAAGUAGGUGCUGGCCAGAGGGCAGCCCGGGCUGACAGCCAUUCGCUUGCCUGCUGGGGGAAAGGGGCCUCAGAUCGGACCCUCUGGCCAACCGCAGCCUGGAGCCCACCUCCAGCAGCAGUCCUGCGUCUCUGCCGGAGUGGGAGCGGUCACUGCUGGGGGCUGCGCAGCACGCUUGCGUCUUUUGCAUGCCGCGUUGCCACUACUCUGCCUGUUCUGGAAGGCCUGGGACCCUCCCUUGGAGGGGGCACAGGGUCCUGAGGACACCGUGAGCCAGCCAGGCCUGGCCGCUGGGCCUGACCGGCCCCCCAGCCCCUACACCCCGCUUCUCCCGGACUCUCCCAGCGGACAGCCCCCCAGCCCCACAGCCUGAGCCUCCCAGCUGCCAUGUGCCUGUUGCACACCUGCACACACGCCCUGGCACACAUACACACAUGCGUGCAGGCUUGUGCAGACACUCAGGGAUGGAGCUGCUGCUGAAGGGACUUGUAGGGAGAGGCUCGUCAACAAGCACUGUUCUGGAACCUUCUCUCCACGUGGCCCACAGGCCUGACCACAGGGGCUGUGGGUCCUGCGUCCCCUUCCUCGGGUGAGCCUGGCCUGUCCCGUUCAGCCGUUGGGCCCAGGCUUCCUCCCCUCCAAGGUGAAACACUGCAGUCCCGGUGUGGUGGCUCCCCAUGCAGGACGGGCCAGGCUGGGAGUGCCGCCUUCCUGUGCCAAAUUCAGUGGGGACUCAGUGCCCAGGCCCUGGCCACGAGCUUUGGCCUUGGUCUACCUGCCAGGCCAGGCAAAGCGCCUUUACACAGGCCUCGGAAAACAAUGGAGUGAGCACAAGAUGCCCUGUGCAGCUGCCCGAGGGUCUCCGCCCACCCCGGCCGGACUUUGAUCCCCCCGAAGUCUUCACAGGCACUGCAUCGGGUUGUCUGGCGCCCUUUUCCUCCAGCCUAAACUGACAUCAUCCUAUGGACUGAGCCGGCCACUCUCUGGCCGAAGUGGCCGCAGGCUGUGCCCCCGAGCUGCCCCCACCCCCUCACAGGGUCCCUCAGAUUAUAGGUGCCCAGGCUGAGGUGAAGAGGCCUGGGGGCCCUGCCUUCCGGGCGCUCCUGGACCCUGGGGCAAACCUGUGACCCUUUUCUACUGGAAUAGAAAUGAGUUUUAUCAUCUUUGAAAAAUAAUUCACUCUUGAAGUAAUAAACGUUUAAAAAAAUGGGAUGCCUGCCUCUGUGACAGCCUUGUUUGCUGAGGUCGUGGGGGUGGGGGCCUCUGGGAAGUUCCGGGCUCCUCUUCUCUUGGUCAAUAGCUCCUUUCUGGUGGCUGCCAAGAGCGUCUCUCCCAGGGCCGGGCUGCUGGCUUACCUUCCUGUUGUUUUCAAAUUUCAACCUUGUGCAAUGUUGAGUUUCAUAGAAAUACUGCAUGAGUACGCCCUUGUUUAGAAGCAGCAGGGUCUGAGUCCCAUCCCACAGCCCCCAGUGCAGACGCUUUUGCCACUUUUGCAUGGGGCCCCCUGGAUGUGUUUCUGUGCAUUUAUCUACAAAUCCUGGUGCCCAUAGGACAUGCCCCGUGUUGUUCUAGGCCUUUGCUUUCUGCUCGUUACAUAAAUGGUGAAGAAGAGAAGCGGGUAAGAGAACAGAUUGGAGCCAUCUAAAAGUUCUCAUCUUAAGUGUAGAUCAUUGCAAAGGAUGGAAUUUUCUCCGAUUGUCAUCAUCGUUGAUGUUUGAAUAUGAGACCAUUUCAUCAGUAUUUAAGUGUGCCCGCUGGGAUCUAACUAGGAGAGGAGAGGGUAUUCACUGCCGAACAUUUCAAAGAAUAUACGAACAAGCUCUUUUAUGGUCAGAAAUGUUAGCCCUUUUCCCCUUAAACUUGUAUUUCCUUUCUUCUUCCCUCCUAAAAUUUUAUCUAAAUGAUAUUUAUAUUUGAUGCUUUUAAGCCUUUUAUUAAUCACUCCUAUACUUGCCUGCAACAUAAAUAUAUAAGUUGAAGCAAA